CUCUCUUUCCGGUGUGGAGUCUGGAGACGACGUGCAGGUAGGAGGCCCGGGCGCGACAAUCGGGGGGCAUCCUGCGGCGAGGGGACCCUGUGGGGCUUGGGACGAGAGACGGGGGUCUUUCCGUGGGAACCGAGCUAGGUGCCGGGCAAGAGACGCGCGGCUGGCCCACCUGGAUCCUGGCCAACUCGGGAUUGAGUUCGUUCCUGGUCUCAGAAGGCCCGUUUUGCUUUCAGGGAGGAGCUUGUGAAGUAAGGAAAUGGCACCUCGAAAGGGGAAGGAAAAGAAGGAAGAACAGGUCAUCAGCCUCGGACCUCAGGUGGCUGAAGGAGAGAAUGUAUUUGGUGUCUGCCAUAUCUUUGCAUCCUUCAAUGACACUUUUGUCCAUGUCACUGAUCUUUCUGGCAAGGAAACCAUCUGCCGUGUGACUGGUGGGAUGAAGGUAAAGGCAGACCGAGAUGAAUCCUCACCAUAUGCUGCUAUGUUGGCUGCCCAGGAUGUGGCCCAGAGGUGCAAGGAGCUGGGUAUCACCGCCCUACACAUCAAACUCCGGGCCACAGGAGGAAAUAGGACCAAGACCCCUGGACCUGGGGCCCAGUCGGCCCUCAGAGCCCUUGCCCGCUCGGGUAUGAAGAUCGGGCGGAUUGAGGAUGUCACCCCCAUCCCCUCUGACAGCACUCGCAGGAAGGGGGGUCGCCGUGGUCGCCGUCUGUGAACAAGAUUCCUCAAAAUAUUUUCUGUUAAUAAAUUGCCUUCAUGUAAACUGUUUCAACUCCAGCCUUCUCUCCUUCAUCAGGGGCUACUCAGGCAUUUGAUUUCUUCCUCCUAUUUGGCUUCUUGGGAGAAAGGAGCCUGAGGAGAGCUGAGAUCCUGGUGCUGCAUUUGGGGUCUUUUCCAUGCUACUUGCGGCAUUAAGUUGCCUUGGUCAUCUAAAGCAGACCAAGGCGUUGGAGACCUCGUUUUGAGUGGAGAUGCUGGUUCUAAAUAUGGACCAAUUCUUAAAGAGCCAGAGUGGGAACUGUUGAUCCAAGUGUAGCCUGAAGCGAAAGAGGAGCCUUCCAGACCCAUGCCAUAUAUAAACACACGUGGGUGUGCAUUCUCCCCCCACACCUUCUGUGCAAAGCUGGGAGCUCACUCCACUGCGUCUUGCUUUUUUUCACUUGGCAGAUCUUGGAGAUUGUUCCACAUCAGUACAUAAAGUACAUAAAGAUUGUCACCCCACAAAUACACACCAAGUCCUAUUUUCAUCAGCGAUAAAAAAGAAAAGUUCUUGCUUUCCGGAAGCUUGCAUGCGGCUCUGAGUACCCAGUGACACCAGAUGGUACUCAGCGUUUUGCAAGGGAUUACCACAAGGCCCCGUGAUGGUGCCUGCCAUGGUUAGGACAGGCUGGUGGCUGGGUAGGGUUAGUGAGACCCAGUGGAGAGGAUGCUGUGUGUCACAGGCUGGAGAGGUGAGACCAUUGAGGUAGUCAGUUGUAGAGGAAAGAAACCAGCAAGAGGGGAAAAUCUGUUGGGAUGCUGCUUUUAGCCUUUGAUGGCGUGUUCCAGGCAGAGGGAAUAAGCAAAUAAAUGGGUCCUGAGACAAGGGGUUACUGUGAUGAGGCGGCGUUGGUUACAUGCCAAACCUUGCUAGGGAUUUUAAUAACAACAUUGAAUCUUAACCUGAUGAAAUAACAGUACUCCUGGGGAGGCGGGAGGGAUAGCAUUAGGAGAUAUACCUAAUGCUAAAUGACGAGUUAAUGGGUGCAGCACACCAACAUGGCACAUGUAUACAUAUGUAACAAACCUGCACGUUGUGCACAUGUACCCUAAAACUUAAAGUAUAAUAAAAAAAAAAAGCUUGCAAAAAAAAUAUAACAGUACUCCUUAAAUUGUUAAAAGUCAUGAAAGUCAAGGACAGGAGAUUAAGGAGGCGUGAAAACUAAAUGCCCAUUGUGGUAUCCUGGAUUGGAUUCUGGAACCAGAAUAGGGUAUUAGUAUAAAAACUAGUGAAAUAGGAUAAAGGCAGGGCACAGUGGUUCACGCCUAUAAUCCCAACACUUUGGGAAGCCGAGACAGGAGGACGGAUUGAGCCCAGGAGUUUGAGACCAGCCUGGGCAACACAGGGAGACCCCGUCUCUACAAAAAAUAAAAAAUUAGCUGGGCAUGGUGGCACACGUCUGUACUGCCAGCUACUUGGGAGGCUGAGGUGGGAGAAUUGCCUGAGCCUGGGAAGUGGAGGCCGCAGUGAGCUGUGAUUGCAUCACUACAUUCAGCCUGGGUCACAGAGCAAGAUCCUAUCUCAAAAACUAAAUAAGUAAAUAAUAAAUUAAAAAAUAUGAAUAAAGUCUGGAGUUAAAGUCUGGAAUAAAGCUAGUAGUAAUGUA